CUACAGGAGGUUUUGACGGCUGGAUGCUGCAGGGCAUCCCCUCGCCUGGAGGAGGUUCACUUGUGGCCAGGUUCCCAGCACACCCACUUGCUCACUGGGGCCCUGGGGACACCGCCACACUCGAGCCCAUCCUACGGCCUCAAUCCUUACCAGUCCCCAGGCCAUGGACUGCCACACUGUAGGUCUUCAAUCAAGGUUCAGUGGAGUUUCGAAUGUACACACACCCUGAAAGACAGCGCGGCCACCUCAGAAAACAACGCGCGCCCAGCUGGCUCCCCUCCGACAGGGCCCACGGCUACUGGGUCGGCCUCCUCCGGACCCUGAGCACAGCCUGGUAUGCGUGCGGGCUCGGAAUACGGAUCUGAGCAGAAGAAAUGCGAGUGGAGAGCGGUUCUGCGCAGGAAAGAGGAAUUUUGUUGGAAAGCCUGUCGACGUUGCUAGAAAAGACCACAGCAUCUCACGAGGGGCGUGCGCCGGGAAACCGGGAGUUGACGGACCUCCUGCCCCCCGAGGUCUGCAGUCUCCUGAACCCAGCAGCCAUCUACGCCAACAACGAGAUCAGCCUGCGUGACGUUGAGGUCUACGGCUUUGACUACGACUACACCCUGGCCCAGUAUGCAGACGCACUGCACCCCGAGAUCUUCAGUACCGCCCGUGACAUCCUGAUCGAGCACUACAAGUACCCAGAAGGGAUUCGGAAGUAUGACUACAACCCCAGCUUUGCCAUCCGUGGCCUCCACUAUGACAUUCAGAAGAGCCUUCUGAUGAAGAUUGACGCCUUCCACUACGUGCAGCUGGGGACAGCCUACAGGGGCCUCCAGCCUGUGCCAGACGAGGAGGUGAUUGAGCUGUAUGGGGGUACCCAGCACAUCCCACUAUACCAGAUGAGUGGCUUCUAUGGCAAGGGUCCCUCCAUUAAGCAGUUCAUGGACAUCUUCUCGCUACCGGAGAUGGCUCUGCUGUCCUGUGUGGUGGACUACUUUCUGGGCCACAGCCUGGAGUUUGACCAAGCACAUCUCUACAAGGACGUGACGGACGCCAUCCGAGACGUGCAUGUGAAGGGCCUCAUGUACCAGUGGAUCGAGCAGGACAUGGAGAAGUACAUCCUGAGAGGGGAUGAGACGUUUGCUGUCCUGAGCCGCCUGGUGGCCCAUGGGAAACAGCUGUUCCUCAUCACCAACAGUCCUUUCAGCUUCGUAGACAAGGGGAUGCGGCACAUGGUGGGUCCCGAUUGGCGCCAGCUCUUCGAUGUGGUCAUUGUCCAGGCAGACAAGCCCAGCUUCUUCACUGACCGGCGCAAGCCUUUCAGAAAACUCGAUGAGAAGGGCUCACUUCAGUGGGACCGGAUCACCCGCUUGGAAAAGGGCAAGAUCUAUCGGCAGGGAAACCUGUUUGACUUCUUACGCUUGACGGAAUGGCGUGGCCCCCGCGUGCUCUACUUCGGGGACCACCUCUAUAGUGAUCUGGCGGAUCUCAUGCUGCGGCACGGCUGGCGCACAGGCGCCAUCAUCCCCGAGCUGGAGCGUGAGAUCCGCAUCAUCAACACGGAGCAGUACAUGCACUCGCUGACGUGGCAGCAGGCGCUCACGGGGCUGCUGGAGCGCAUGCAGACCUAUCAGGACGCGGAGUCGAGGCAGGUGCUGGCUGCCUGGAUGAAAGAGCGGCAGGAGCUGAGGUGCAUCACCAAGGCCCUGUUCAAUGCGCAGUUCGGCAGCAUCUUCCGCACCUUCCACAACCCCACCUACUUCUCAAGGCGCCUCGUGCGCUUCUCUGACCUCUACAUGGCCUCCCUCAGCUGCCUGCUCAACUACCGCGUGGACUUCACCUUCUACCCACGCCGUACGCCGCUGCAGCACGAGGCACCCCUCUGGAUGGACCAGCUCUGCACCGGCUGCAUGAAGACCCCCUUCCUUGGUGACAUGGCCCACAUCCGCUGAGGGCACCUUUAUUGUCUGGGACAGGCCCUCAGCCCCUCCUGCCCCAUCCACCCAGACAAGCAAUAAAAGUGGUCUCCUCCCUG